GCCAUCGCCGCAGAUCCAGCGCCCAGAGAGACACCAGAGAACCCACCAUGGCCCCCUUUGAGCCCCUGGCUUCUGGCAUCCUGUUGUUGCUGUGGCUGAUAGCCCCCAGCAGGGCCUGCACCUGUGUCCCACCCCACCCACAGACGGCCUUCUGCAAUUCCGACCUCGUCAUCAGGGCCAAGUUCGUGGGGACACCAGAAGUCAACCAGACCACCUUAUACCAGCGUUAUGAGAUCAAGAUGACCAAGAUGUAUAAAGGGUUCCAAGCCUUAGGGGAUGCCGCUGACAUCCGGUUCGUCUACACCCCCGCCAUGGAGAGUGUCUGCGGAUACUUCCACAGGUCCCACAACCGCAGCGAGGAGUUUCUCAUUGCUGGAAAACUGCAGGAUGGACUCUUGCACAUCACUACCUGCAGUUUUGUGGCUCCCUGGAACAGCCUGAGCUUAGCUCAGCGCCGGGGCUUCACCAAGACCUACACUGUUGGCUGUGAGGAAUGCACAGUGUUUCCCUGUUUAUCCAUCCCCUGCAAACUGCAGAGUGGCACUCAUUGCUUGUGGACGGACCAGCUCCUCCAAGGCUCUGAAAAGGGCUUCCAGUCCCGUCACCUUGCCUGCCUGCCUCGGGAGCCAGGGCUGUGCACCUGGCAGUCCCUGCGGUCCCAGAUAGCCUGAAUCCUGCCCGGAGUGGAAGCUGAAGCCUGCACAGUGUCCACCCUGUUCCCACUCCCAUCUUUCUUCCGGACAAUGAAAUAAAGAGUUACCACCCAGCA